GAAGGCUGAGCGCGGGCUCUCAAGGAAAGUAGUCGCGGAAUCUCAGUUAGCGGUGGAGAGGCAGUAUGUCCGGUUCAAUGGCGACUGCGGAAGCUAGCGGCAGCGAUGGGAAAGGGCAGGAAGUCGAGACCUCAGUCACCUAUUACCGGUUGGAGGAGGUGGCAAAGCGCAACUCCUUGAAGGAACUGUGGCUUGUGAUCCAUGGGCGAGUCUACGAUGUCACCCGCUUCCUCAACGAGCACCCUGGAGGAGAAGAGGUUCUGCUGGAACAAGCUGGUGUAGAUGCAAGUGAAAGCUUUGAAGAUGUAGGACACUCUUCUGAUGCCAGAGAAAUGCUAAAGCAGUACUACAUUGGUGAUAUCCAUCCGAGUGACCUUAAACCUGAAAGUGGUAGCAAGGACCCUUCAAAAAAUGAUACAUGCAAAAGUUGCUGGGCAUAUUGGAUUUUACCCAUCAUAGGCGCUGUUCUCUUAGGUUUCCUGUACCGCUACUACACAUCGGAAAGCAAAUCCUCCUGAGGAGGCCUUGCUGAAGUUAGAAAGUGCAUCCACUUUGGGGCGAAAACUAGAGACUUGCUUGGGGGCUGCAGAAGUGCCCUCUCCUCGAAUCCUGCCAGUUGCAUUCUUCCCCCUUGGAGCCAAGACGAUUGGCCAGACAUCACCUCAGAUCUGAGACCAGCGUCUUCCAUCUCUCAGAGCCUUACUCCCAAAGUACCUGCUCACUGUUCCGUGUUGAACAAUUGCCGGUGUUUCCUCUCUUCACUGGUUUCCAUGAGUACCCUUAUAUUUCACAACUUUCUGUUCAUAAGUUAUAGUGACAUUGCUCUUUGGUAAAAAUGCCUGCUUUCCAAUACUUUGAUUGCAUAUUAGACAUUCUUAACAGGGCGGCAGUCUAGUGUUGAAAGUUUUAUUUUUCCAUUUUUCUUUUAAGUAAAUUUUUUUUAAAAAAUUCUGAUUUAGGGCUAGGUGUGGUGGCUCAGGCCUGUAAUCCUGGCACUUUGGGAGGCCAAGGUGGGAAGAUCGCUUGAGGCCAAGAGUUCAAGACCAGCCUGGGCAACAUAGCGAGACCCCUAUCUGUAUUAAAAAAAAAUCUGAUUUAAUUCUUUUAUUUAUCAUAAGGGGUUUAAUUCCUGAAGUAAAGGUUUGCACCUAUUAAACUUAAAACUGCCAAAUGAUUUUUGUUCUUUUAUGUGCGUGAUAAAAAUACAAAGAAUGGUGUGGCCACCUCCUCCCUUUCAAGCUAGGGCAGCAGGUAGCUCUUCCCAGCCCCUGAGCCCAGCCCCUUCCCAAGUGGUGCCGGACAAAAAACUACAUGGCCCUUUCGUGUCUUGGGGGUGGAAAGGUAGGGAUGAAUUGGGGUGAUAGAACCCUGGUGAAUUCAGAGUAAUCUUUCUUUAGAAAACUGGUGUUUUCUAAAGAAACAGGAUAGGAGUUUAGAGAAGGCACCAAAGCUUUCACUUUGGUUUGGCACCAGUUUCUAACCAUCUGUUUUUUCUACCCUAGCUAUCUUUUAUUGGUAAAAUAUAAAUGUAUAAUUAUGUUUGUAGAGCUUUACCAAGGAGUUUCCCUCCUUUUUUGUUUGUUGAUUAGCAAAUUUUUGAUUCUCCAUUUUCCAAAAGUAAGAGACUCCAGCAUGGCCUUCUGUUUGCCCCGCAGUAAAGUAACUUCCAUAUAAAAUGGUAUUUGAAAGUGAGAGUUCAUGACAACAGACCGUUUUCCAUUUCAUCUGUAUUUUAUCUCCGUGACUCCAACUUGUGGGUUUGUUCUGUUUUUCCAUGAGAAUAAAAUACUGGCGGUUUUUUUCUCAGAUGUGUGUUCAUUGAGAAGUAGGUUACUAGAAUUAUGUUACUGUGUCUUAUUGGUUCAAUGAUGAUUUCUCUGGCAUAUUAGACUUUUAUUUUUUCCCCCAUGGAAGCACUUGAGGAAAUAAAUAGUACACUGGCUGUUUUCUGCCAGCAACUGUGGUGAUUUUUCUCCCUGUCCUUUGAGAAUUGCUAGUCUGCUUCUGAGCCAUUGUCAUAUCCAGCAGGGAGCAGCUUGGUUCAAGAAGGACCAUAGAGGCUGCUCAGCAUCUCCUCCCUCCCUCCCAGCUUGCCAGGGAUUUGAUGAGACAGGAAACUGCCCAGCAAACCAGGGACUGCCCAUGUAAACUAUUUAAGAAAAAGUUCAACCCAGGUCUUGUAUCCUGUGAUUUAGCAGUUGAAUGAAUACAGAAUUCAUCAAAAUAAUAUUAACCUUGUACUUGCACACUUGGAUAUAUUUGGGAGUAAUUUUAGGAGAUUUCUGGCUGACUUUUAUUAUCAGGGAUAUGGGUUUAGUAAAGCUUUUAUCUUUAGAAAAAUGUUUGUAUGCAUUAUAAGAUGCUACUUUUAAGACAAUAUUGAAAAAAACUUUGGUUAUUAUUUAACAAAAGUGGUAUGACUUGAUGCUUCUCUAUUUAAAGGCAAGGAAGGAUUGGUAUAUGAUUGCCUGUAAUAAAUAAAUUGCGUGAUUAUUGGAGUACAUUGGGGUAAAAGUAAAGAACAGAGGAGUAUUGAGGAGCUUGAAAGGGAACAUUCAAACUAAAGCCAAGCCUGAAGAUAACUUGAAUCAGUUGUAAAAGUGUGUUGGCAAUGUCCGAAAUUGAAUGAAAAACAUCUGGCUUAUAAGAAAUGUUAAAGAACUACCAUCUUAAGUAAAAUUGGUGUUUUUGUUAUUUUUAAGGUAAAUGCCAAUGCAAAAGGUAUGUUUUUCUACUUCACAUUGGUUUUCUUUUCCUGUUUACAUCUGCACUUGUUUUUUGCUGAGAGCCAGAGGAAAAGAUAAUUAGACUUUGUCUCUUCCACCCAUGAAAUCCCCCAGUACCCAGGGCUUCUUCUGAACUACUGCCGAUGUGAUGUCACUUUGUAUCUGGAAAAUCACUUUGGGGUCCAUUUACUGUUAUUUUGUUGCCUACAAAAACAGCCAGGUGAAAGCUAAAUCUUGUGUGAGAGUUUGCAGAGGUUUUUCUAUACAAUAAAGUAGUAUAGCACACUAGCCAAAUCCAUCCAAAAGGACCUUUUUUUUAGGAAGUAGACUUGAAUUCACAAAACAGUCUUGACAUGGGUAGCUGGUGAAAAACCCUCUGGAGAGCAAGUGGAGCCAGUCCCCAUUGGCUGACAGUGCCACCUGGAGCUGGUCUCUGGGGUGUUCGGUUGUUUAUUCCUGAGGAAGACUAGCUGCUGCUGCUGCUGCUGCUGCAAACUGUACUGUACACAUCAUGGCUGCUGGACACGAAGGAGGAGGUGAGAGAAGUUUCAUGCUACCGAAAUAGAGGGUGUUGGUACCACUGCCCCUGGCCUGAGAGCCAGGGUUUAAACCUGCCUCAGUAGAGUCUAGUUUGAAAUGACACCAAAAUUCCUCAGCCCCUACUCAGCAAUUGGUUUUGGUUUCCAAAUGACUUCUGCAUUUGUAAAGAUAACAGAGUGGUGGGGUCAAAGUUUAUCUUGUGUUUAGAUCUCUUCAAGACUGCUUAAGCAAAAACAAAAAUCCCUUGGAACCUAUCGUUUGAGCCUGUAAAGUUGUUUUAGCAGUUGUCAUAAAUGCAUAUGUUGUGAAAUCAGAACACUGUCGAGUUUAUACUCAUUUAGCUGCAAUGUGGGACAAUGAAAAAUGCUUUACAGGCCUGGAGUAUCAUUACUUAUGGUAUCUCCUGCUUUAAAAUCUCAAGCGAUAUCUAUCUGGUUAAAUUCCAUUUUAGGAGAUUGAGAUGCAGAACGUUAAUGUUCAUUACCUCCUCCUACCCCAAGAGAAAUGGAUUCAGACAUGUCUUGUCUCAACAAGAAAUUGAUUUUUUUUUAAACUAUCUUAUUCUGUUGCCAAAUAUCACAGAAGUAAUGAGGAGUUUAGUUACAUUUGGCUGUUGUGCUCUGAAAGAGCCAGGUUUGGAAUUUGUGGGGGUGAUCUAGGAAGAAGGUUCCAAAGAAGCAGAGGCAUUUGUCAAGUUACCUACCCUAUAUCCAGCAUCCUCCUCAUGAGCUUCAGUAGCUGCUCUUUGCCCACGCUUGUAUCCUACGUUUGCUAUUUGGGCAAACCAUUACUUCAGUUAUUUAACUUCCCUUUUUUUUUAACUUCACCUUUGACUAUGAACAAGUAACGGUAACAUUCCUUUUGUGUAUUCAAUAAUGCAGUUAGUUUACCUUUUUCAGAAUAUUUUGAACAAAGAUCUUUGUCUCUUUCUGCUGGAAUGCGCACACAGUGAACGUUUGUUAGAACUACACACAAUAAAGACACUGUUUUCCUUUU